AGGGAGGCCGCUCCCCACAAUCUCGGGAGGGCACUUCCCCCAGCACCCAAGCGCGAGACCCGGGGCUCGCGGCCAGAGUUUCCGACUUCUUCCGGAGGAAGAAGGGCUGUUUUUGGCAACUCUGUGUUGGUGCGACCUGACCCUUUUCAGUUUCUAAGGCAGAAGCUAAGGAUGGGGGAGAGGCAGAUUCUGGCUGGAUUCUCCCGCUCCCACGGUUGCCGCUGUCCUUGGUCCUGAACUUUCGUUCUCCUUCGCCUUCUCUUGGGUUGACACCUAGUCGGGGAGGGAGGCUUGGGUGCCAGACCCGUUUCUACCCGGCAGUGCAGGCGACGGUGGCGGCAGUAGCGGAGGGUGACCGCCCGGCUCUCGGCCCGGCUCUAUGAUGGACCGAGAGCCCCUCUAGGGUGGUAUGCGGAGACAAGAGACACCUCUAAGCACCAGACAGAGCGCUUCCCUAUCCCUGUCUGAGGCGGGCAGCCCUUGAGUGCUUCCUCUUGAAGAGCAGAGAGCCUGGCCACCCAGUGGCUCCACCGCCCUGAUGGAUCCACUGAAUCUGUCCUGGUAUGAUGAUGAUCUGGAGAGGCAGAACUGGAGCCGGCCCUUCAACGGGUCAGACGGGAAGGCGGACAGACCCCACUACAACUACUAUGCCACACUGCUCACCCUGCUCAUCGCUGUCAUCGUCUUCGGCAACGUGCUGGUGUGCAUGGCUGUGUCCCGCGAGAAGGCGCUGCAGACCACCACCAACUACCUGAUCGUCAGCCUCGCAGUGGCCGACCUCCUCGUCGCCACACUGGUCAUGCCCUGGGUUGUCUACCUGGAGGUGGUAGGUGAGUGGAAAUUCAGCAGGAUUCACUGUGACAUCUUCGUCACUCUGGACGUCAUGAUGUGCACGGCGAGCAUCCUGAACUUGUGUGCCAUCAGCAUCGACAGGUACACAGCUGUGGCCAUGCCCAUGCUGUACAAUACGCGCUACAGCUCCAAGCGCCGGGUCACCGUCAUGAUCUCCAUCGUCUGGGUCCUGUCCUUCACCAUCUCCUGCCCACUCCUCUUCGGACUCAAUAACGCAGACCAGAACGAGUGCAUCAUUGCCAACCCGGCCUUCGUGGUCUACUCCUCCAUCGUCUCCUUCUACGUGCCCUUCAUUGUCACCCUGCUGGUCUACAUCAAGAUCUACAUUGUCCUCCGCAGACGCCGCAAGCGAGUCAACACCAAACGCAGCAGCCGAGCUUUCAGGGCCCACCUGAGGGCUCCACUAAAGGGCAACUGUACUCACCCCGAGGACAUGAAACUCUGCACCGUUAUCAUGAAGUCUAAUGGGAGUUUCCCAGUGAACAGGCGGAGAGUGGAGGCUGCCCGGCGAGCCCAGGAGCUGGAGAUGGAGAUGCUCUCCAGCACCAGCCCACCCGAGAGGACCCGGUACAGCCCCAUCCCACCCAGCCACCACCAGCUGACUCUCCCCGACCCGUCCCACCAUGGUCUCCACAGCACUCCCGACAGCCCCGCCAAACCAGAGAAGAAUGGGCAUGCCAAAGACCACCCCAAGAUUGCCAAGAUCUUUGAGAUCCAGACCAUGCCCAAUGGCAAAACCCGGACCUCCCUCAAGACCAUGAGCCGUAGGAAGCUCUCCCAGCAGAAGGAGAAGAAAGCCACUCAGAUGCUCGCCAUUGUUCUCGGCGUGUUCAUCAUCUGCUGGCUGCCCUUCUUCAUCACACACAUCCUGAACAUACACUGUGACUGCAACAUCCCGCCUGUCCUGUACAGCGCCUUCACGUGGCUGGGCUAUGUCAACAGCGCCGUGAACCCCAUCAUCUACACCACCUUCAACAUUGAGUUCCGCAAGGCCUUCCUGAAGAUCCUCCACUGCUGACUCUGCUGCCUGCCCGCACAGCAGCCUGCUUCCCACCUCCCUGCCCAGGCCGGCCAGCCUCACCCUUGCGAACCGUGAGCAGGAAGGCCUGGGUGGAUCGGCCUCCUCUUCACCCCGGCAGGCCCUGCAGUGUUCGCUUGGCUCCAUGCUCCUCACUGCCCGCACACCCUCACUCUGCCAGGGCAGUGCUAGUGAGCUGGGCAUGGUACCAGCCCUGGGGCUGGGCCCCCCAGCUCAGGGGCAGCUCAUAGAGUCCCCCCUCCCACCUCCAGUCCCCCUAUCCUUGGCACCAAAGAUGCAGCCGCCUUCCUUGACCUUCCUCUGGGGCUCUAGGGUUGCUGGAGCCUGAGUCAGGGCCCAGAGGCUGAGUUUUCUCUUUGUGGGGCUUGGCGUGGAGCAGGCGGUGGGGAGAGAUGGACAGUUCACACCCUGCAAGGCCCACAGGAGGCAAGCAAGCUCUCUUGCCGAGGAGCCAGGCAACUUCAGUCCUGGGAGACCCAUGUAAAUACCAGACUGCAGGUUGGACCCCAGAGAUUCCCAAGCCAAAAACCUUAGCUCCCUCCCGCACCCCGAUGUGGACCUCUACUUUCCAGGCUAGUCCGGACCCACCUCACCCCGUUACAGCUCCCCAAGUGGUUUCCACAUGCUCUGAGAAGAGGAGCCCUCAUCUUGAAGGGCCCAGGAGGGUCUAUGGGGAGAGGAACUCCUUGGCCUAGCCCACCCUGCUGCCUUCUGACGGCCCUGCAAUGUAUCCCUUCUCACAGCACAUGCUGGCCAGCCUGGGGCCUGGCAGGGAGGUCAGGCCCUGGAACUCUAUCUGGGCCUGGGCUAGGGGACAUCAGAGGUUCUUUGAGGGACUGCCUCUGCCACACUCUGACGCAAAACCACUUUCCUUUUCUAUUCCUUCUGGCCUUUCCUCUCUCCUGUUUCCCUUCCCUUCCACUGCCUCUGCCUUAGAGGAGCCCACGGCUAAGAGGCUGCUGAAAACCAUCUGGCCUGGCCUGGCCCUGCCCUGAGGAAGGAGGGGAAGCUGCAGCUUGGGAGAGCCCCUGGGGCCUAGACUCUGUAACAUCACUAUCCAUGCACCAAACUAAUAAAACUUUGACGAGUCACCUUCCAGGA